AGGGCCCGGAGCCGGCGAGUGCUCCCGGGAACUCUGCCUGCGCGGCGGCAGCGACCGGAGGCCAGGCCCAGCACGCCGGAGCUGGCCUGCUGGGGAGGGGCGGGAGGCGCGCGCGGGAGGGUCCGCCCGGCCAGGGCCCCGGGCGCUCGCAGAGGCCGGCCGCGCUCCCAGCCCGCCCGGAGCCCAUGCCCGGCGGCUGGCCAGUGCUGCGGCAGAAGGGGGGGCCCGGCUCUGCAUGGCCCCGGCUGCUGACAUGACUUCUUUGCCACUCGGUGUCAAAGUGGAGGACUCCGCCUUCGGCAAGCCGGCGGGGGGAGGCGCGGGCCAGGCCCCCAGCGCCGCCGCGGCCACGGCAGCCGCCAUGGGCGCGGACGAGGAGGGGGCCAAGCCCAAAGUGUCCCCUUCGCUCCUGCCCUUCAGCGUGGAGGCGCUCAUGGCCGACCACAGGAAGCCGGGGGCCAAGGAGAGCGCCCUGGCGCCCUCCGAGGGCGUGCAGGCGGCGGGUGGCUCGGCGCAGCCACUGGGCGUCCCGCCGGGGUCGCUGGGAGCCCCGGACGCGCCCUCUUCGCCGCGGCCGCUCGGCCAUUUCUCGGUGGGGGGACUCCUCAAGCUGCCAGAAGAUGCGCUCGUCAAAGCCGAGAGCCCCGAGAAGCCCGAGAGGACCCCGUGGAUGCAGAGCCCCCGCUUCUCCCCGCCGCCGGCCAGGCGGCUGAGCCCCCCAGCCUGCACCCUCCGCAAACACAAGACGAACCGUAAGCCGCGGACGCCCUUCACCACCGCGCAGCUGCUGGCGCUGGAGCGCAAGUUCCGCCAGAAGCAGUACCUGUCCAUCGCCGAGCGCGCGGAGUUCUCCAGCUCGCUCAGCCUCACUGAGACGCAGGUGAAGAUAUGGUUCCAGAACCGCCGCGCCAAGGCAAAGAGACUACAAGAGGCAGAGCUGGAGAAGCUGAAGAUGGCCGCCAAGCCCAUGCUGCCACCGGCUGCCUUCGGCCUCUCCUUCCCUCUCGGCGGCCCCGCAGCUGUAGCGGCCGCGGCGGGUGCCUCGCUCUACGGUGCCUCUGGCCCCUUCCAGCGCGCCGCGCUGCCUGUGGCGCCCGUGGGACUCUACACGGCCCAUGUGGGCUACAGCAUGUACCACCUGACAUAGAGGGUCCCAGGUCGCCCACCUGUGGGCCAGCCGAUUCCUCCAGCCCUGGUGCUGUACCCCCGACGUGCUCCCCUGCUCGGCACCGCCAGCCGCCUUCCCUUUAACCCUCACACUGCUCCAGUUUCACCUCUUUGCUCCCUGAGUUCACUCUCCGAAGUCUGAUCCCUGCCAAAAAGUGGCUGGAAGAGUCCCUUAGUACUCUUCUAGCAUUUAGAUCUACACUCUCGAGUUAAAGAUGGGGAAACUGAGGGCAGAGAGGUUAACAGAUUUAUCUAAGGUCCCCAGCAGAAUUGACAGUUGAACAGAGCUAGAGGCCAUGUCUCCUGCAUAGCUUUUCCCUGUCCUGACACCAGGCAAGAAAAGCGCAGAGAAAUCGGUGUCUGACGAUUUUGGAAAUGAGAACAAUCUCAAAAAAAAAAAAAAAAAAAAAAAAAAAAAAAAAAAAGAAAAGAGAAAAAAAAGACUAGCCAGCCAGGAAGAUGAAUCCUAGCUUCUUCCAUUGGAAAAUUUAAGACAAGUUCAACAACAAAACAUUUGCUCUGGGGGGCAGGGAAAACACAGAUGUGUUGCAAAGGUAGGUUGAAGGGACCUCUCUCUUACCAGUACCAGAAACACAAUUGUAAAAUUAAAAAAAAAAAAAAACUCUUUCUAUUUAACAGUACAUUUGUGUGGCUCUCAAACAUCCCUUUGGAAGGGAUUGUGUGUACUAUGUAAUAUACUGUAUAUUUGAAAUUUUAUUAUCAUUUAUAUUAUAGCUAUAUUUGUUAAAUAAAUUAAUUUUAAGCUACAAAAA